ACGGGCAAGGGCCGCCAUUUUGACUGAGCAACCCUAGUGACAGGAGCCGAAGCAGCAGCGCAGGUUGUCCCCGUUUCCCCUCCCCCUUCCCUUCUCCGGUUGCCUUCCCGGGCCCCUUACACUCCACAGUCCCGGUCCCGCCAUGUCCCAGAAACAAGAAGAAGAGAACCCUGCGGAGGAGACCGGCGAGGAGAAGCAGGACACGCAGGAGAAAGAAGGUAUUCUGCCUGAGAGAGCUGAAGAGGCAAAGCUAAAGGCCAAAUACCCAAGCCUAGGACAAAAGCCUGGAGGCUCCGACUUCCUCAUGAAGAGACUCCAGAAAGGGGAUUAUAAAUCAUUACAUUGGAGUGUGCUUCUCUGUGCGGAUGAAAUGCAAAAGUACUUUGACUCAGGAGACUACAACAUGGCCAAAGCCAAGAUGAAGAAUAAGCAGCUGCCAAGUGCAGGACCAGACAAGAACCUGGUGACUGGUGAUCACAUCCCCACCCCACAGGAUCUGCCCCAGAGAAAGUCCUCGCUCGUCACCAGCAAGCUUGCGGGGUAACCUGAGCCCCCCUCUCCUCCCCUUCCUCAACCACUGGACGUUUAUAUAUUAUAGGCAGGGAUGAAAUGGGCACCUAGUCAGAUCUUCUCAGCUUGCUAGCCAGAAAUGACUGUGAUUCUGCUGGGGGCUGCUGAGAAGGUAAUGUAGGUUGAAAAGGGGCUCUAAGUUUAUUUAUUUCGUUAGAUUGACACUUCCACACACUCCCUGUAGUCCAGGUAGGGCCCAGAAAUAGGAAAGGCUAGGAUUGGAUAAUGCUGCAAAUGCUUUUUUUGUGUGAGAAACUGGAGAGAUGUGAUUUCUCCUUUUGGGAGAGAAUGUCCCAAAAUUGAUUAGGCUGAGCCUUGGGAAUAGUUUGGCAGGUUUAACAUCCCAAGGCUAACCUAACGUAGUUGGGAAAGGUAGAUUGAAUGAGACAUGUUUUCUGUGCUUCUAAGUGUUCUGUCCCUUAGGCUGCUAUUGCUUCAUGUUUCCAUUAUGGCAGGUUUAGAGAAUCCUUAAAAAGAAAAAUUGACUUGCUUGCCUAAAACUACAGUGCCCCCUUAGCCUCCAUUACUUAGUAUCUCUUACAGUUUGCUCUGGCUCUCAAAUAAUAUAAAGAUUGAUGAACAUUAUUCACAGAAAAUGGGCACCUUCUCUCUCUCUUCCAGCAUGUUGCUUUUGAAAGUAUCAUGGGAUAGUGGGACGAGCACUGGUUUAGGAGUCAAGAUAUCUGGGUUCUCACUCUACUCAGUCCCAGCAGAGCUGUUGUAUAACCUUGAUUAAGUCAUUUAGCCUCUCUGGAUUUCUAUUUCCUCAUCUGUAAAAUAGAGUUAAAUGUAUGUAAGAUUGAUUCUGAUUCUGAAGUCUUAACUGCCAGCAGAAAAACUCCAUACUGUUCAUUGUAAAACUAAAAGUGAGGAAGGCUCGUGGGUGGUGAACCUCUGCUCUGUAAUACUGGGAAAGUACUACAGAGGGGAACCAUUUGAGGGAUACAUGAGGAGAGAGUAAAUUGAGGUUUGGGGAUUAUAAAUUCAGGCAAGAGAACCUUAUAGAUAUCACAGUCUUGAGGGUCAAAAAAAAAUACUUAGGAAGCUAGCCAUGGAAGCUUCUUGCCUCUGACCCAGCCCACUUUCCCAGCCUACCUCUGGGCCUUAGCUGCUAAAAAGCUUCUCUGGCAGCGGAGCUGCAGGCCUGAGGAAACAUGCUCAGUCAUGCACAUGUGUUGACCCAUGUUUCAGAUGCAGUCUGAUGCCAGGUAUAUUGUUAGGGAAAGAGGAAGAAGGGUAAACUGAGCUAGCCCCUGGGGCUGAGUACUCCUGCAGGGCUGGAGGAACAGGUUCUUAGAAGAUGAUUCACCUUGGAGGAAGCUGGGGAAAGUGGUUAGGGAGGGAGAGGAGGAAGACUGAGAAAUCUCUGCAUCCCCAGAACUCAGCAACCCAGCUCUUUUAUCAUGAGGAGAGGUAGCCAUGCUGACUCAUGAACAGGUGGAGGAAAGGGGUUGCAGGUGACCAGCAUCUUCAAUCUAGUUACCACCAGCUUGGCUAGAAUUUUAUUGAACGCAACUUGCUAGUUAUGACAGAGAGGACCAGGGUGAGAACUAAUGCUCAAGAGAGCAAGAUUCUGUAAUCCUCUUGCCCUCUCACAUCACAAAUUCUGAUAUGCCAAACAUUUGGCCCAAUGAGAAUGACUGAUAGACUUGCUGAUGUGCAUGUGGGGGGAUGAGGUGUGUAUAUGCCUUUCUCCUGACUGGCCAUUCAGUGUUCAGGCUGUCAUUCAAAUUGGAUAGGAGAAAGUUGGUGAGGAAGGAAUGGAGAGAGCAGGAUCCCUGGACUCCCUGGUCCCCAAACUCCUUGACUGUCACUUGUAAUUGUAUAUAAUUUUUGUGUUUCUUGCUCCAUUUCCUCAUGCUGUCAUCCUUAAAGUCCAUCUGGGAAGGGGAAAAUGCUGAACACCAUUGUAUAGUUUCUUCAACUGUCCCAGCCAUGUUGUACAUAGAUAUGUCAUGUUAUUAUAUAUAUAAAUAUAUAUAUAAUUUUGUACGUUUUCUUCAUCUCCGAUCUUCUCAAAUUCUGUACUUUUUUUCUUUUCUGUCUGAGCUGCCUUCUCUAUCAUUCAGCUUGAGUCCUCAAGACUACUGGUCACAAUGAGUCUGAUUUUUAGGAAGGAAUAGGAGGAGCAGGGAAAUCAGAAAAACUGUUGGUCUCACUCUGUCUCUCUACCUGGUCAUCUUCAAGGCUAAGAAAACAAACAAGCUACAUUCUGUAUUUGCCAGUUUCCACAGCAUGAAGUACAUAGCUUCCUUAGCAAGGAGUGGUCAUUCCAAAAUCCAAAUGCAAAUUGCUUUGAUUAAACCUAGAUUAUUAAAUCCAUUCAGAACAGCA